CUGGAGUGCAGUGGCGUGAUCUUGGCUCACUGCAACCUCCACCUCCCGGGUUCCAGCGAUUCUCCUGCCUCAGCCUCCCGAGUAACUGGGACUACAGGUGUGUGCCACCACACCCGGCUAACUUCAUAGCAGUUUUUAACAUGUAUAAAGAUAAUACACAGUCAUAAAGUGUGUACAGUGGAAAUCUUGGUUGAAUAUCUCCACUUGUUGGACCACUGUCGGUUUUUAAGUUCAUAACUUGAUGUGAAGUGAUCCAUAUAAUAAAUUUUUCUUUUGGAAGAGCUUUGAUAUAUAGUGCUUUGAGUUCUAUGCCAUGUCACUUAAUAAAUCUCAAGUAUGUAACAAGUAUUUUCUACAAAAUUUCAUUGAGUGCUAUUUAUACUAUAAGAGAGGGCACUAGAGAUGCAAAUUAAUGUCCUAUAAUCAAAUAAGUGCUAUAUUCUAAUUCAUUUCAUAUCUCCUAAUCACCUGAAUUAAAAUCACAGAAAUUUCUAAACCAUCUAUAAUAAUACACUGUACAAAAACUGAGGUGAAGAAAAUAUGUUACUCCUCCUGUAGGAGACAGCUUUUAAAAAAUGAAAAUAUAUUAUCACUUUUAAGUUCCUACUAUGUGACAAGAAUUGUGUUAGGUAAUUUGCAUGUCAUCAUAUCACAAUCCUUCUAGCCAUAAAGUAUCUCUCUUUUUUCUUUUACCUAGUUCUUACUCCUUGUCAUUGUGCUUGAGGGAAUUUGGCAUUGUGUGCUAUCACUUCGAUUAGGGAAACGCAAGAUCCUUAACUAGGCAAUGUAUAGAAUAUUGAGUUGAAAAGCCAUACCUCUUCUCUACAAGUGUCAGGAUCUUCGAAUGGGAAUUUGAUUUCUAUAAUAAUAAUUUAAUAAAAGUGAUUUCUAGCAACAAAAUUUUUUAUCCCAUUGAAUUUAUUAUAACUUAAUUUACUUACGUUAGAAAGUAUUUACAGUUAUAUAAUGAGGAUUUUCUUGAGUUGACUAAAUUUGAGGAAGAAAUUUGCCUUUGAUUGCUUUCCUGGGUUAACAUAUUUCAGAAUUUUUGCCACCUAAUGUAGUAUACUCUUCAUGAAAUUAAACCAGAAACCCACUAACGAGAAAGGUAAUUCACCUACAGAUGCUGUGAGCUAAAAUGUUGUGAGUUGAUCUUGGUUAUUCUUUAUGGCCAUUCCCUUUUUUCCAAGAAAACUAGACCAUUUCUAGAAGGAAGUCAGAUCCUAGUUACAAACAUGUUGCAAGCAGAUUUAAAAAUCUCUACUCCUCCUUCUAUCUUAUUAUACUGAAAUUACAUAGUAAAUUUAAAUACAUACACUUAUACAUAUGGAUGGUAUGUAUGUAUGGAUUUAUGCUGAAGUCUGCAUUAUUAGAGAGCAAACUUGGGCCUAUAGCCAUUAAUUCAGAAACAACUGCUAAUUGUUUGACAGUUACAAAUUGACAUUGCCAAAAAGCAAACUUGGCCUAUUAUUGCUUUGUUCCUUUAAUAUUUCUCUUUUUAUUGUCCUCUUAAUAACACUUUUAUAAAUAUUGUGAUUUAUUCAGUUUCUAAUAAAUAAGCAUAUUUUUAUAUUACUUGAGUCAACAGAACAGCAUUUUGAAACUGUUCACAGAUUCUCAUUCAUAAGCUAAAUACUUAUAGAAAAUAGAUACAGUUACUGAUUUUAUGCAUUCUGUACAAUUUUGCCUAAGAAAUUAAUGCAUAGAAGUGGACUUUUUUAUAUCACCAACAAGAUUGAAAAUAUAAGCAAAAAGUGUUUAUAACUAAUUGUUUUAUAAGAAAGGAACUUCACCUGUUUCUGGAUAUUUUUUCCUCUGGAAUUCAGCCAUAAAAAAGAAUGUAAUCUUGUCAUUUAUGGCAAUGUGGAUGGAACUGGAGGACAUUAAGUGAAAUAAGCCAGGAACAGAAAGUUAAACACUGCAUGUUCUCACUCAUAUGUGAAAGCUAAAAAAUGUUGGUCUCAUAGAAGUAAAAAGUAAGACAGAGGAUAGAUAAUAGAGGCUGGGAAGGGUAGGAGGAAGGAAGGGAUAGGGAGAAAUUUGUUGAAGGAUACAAAAUUUCAGCUAGAUAGAAGAAAUAAGUUCUAGUGUUCUAUACCACUGUAGGAUGACUGUAGUUAACAAUACUAUAUAGUUUCAAAUAGCUGGAAGGAAGAUACUGAACAUUCCUAACACAAAGAAAUGAUAAAUAUUUAGAUAAUGGAUAUGUUAAUUACCUUGAUUUGAUUUCUGUACAUUAUAUGUAUCAGAACAUUAUCUACCCCAUGAAUAUGUAUGAUUAUUAUUUGUUAAUUAAAAAAAUAAAAUUAAAAAAAUCAUACAUGGGCCAGGCAUAGUGGCUCAUGUUUGUAAUCCCAGCACUUUGGGGGGCCGAGGCGGGCAGAUCACUUGAGGUCAGGAGUUUGAGAGCAGCCUAGCCAUCAUGGUGAAACCCCAUCUCUACUAAAAAUACAAAAAUUAGCUGGGUGUGGCGGCGGGUGCCUGUAAUCCCCAGCUCUUCAGGAGGCUGAGGCAGGAGAAUCACUCGAACCUGGGAGGCAGAGGUUACAGUGAGCCGAGAUCAUGCCACUGCACUCCAGCCUGGCGAUAGUGAGAUUCCGACUCACAAAAAAAAAAAAAAAAAAAAAAUCAUACAUAGUAAAAUGGUAGCAUUUUUUGAAUAUGAGUGGAAGCUACAUGAGUGUUUUAAAUAUUUCAUAAUUUUAAAAUCACUGGGUGCAAAUGACUAUAUGAAUAAAAGUGUCCAAUAAACUGUACUCUUAAAAACUAACAAAUAUAUGGGAUAUAUUAGAUACUUGAUGGAUUUAUAUUUGGCAUAAGUAAGGUUAUAUUCACUUUUCAUCCAUCAUUGCAUAUAUGUAUCAAGUAUGUGUGUACUGGCAGUAUUUAUUUAGCCCACUCAGGUAGAAUUUAUUCUUCCCAUAUAAUUACAGGGUAUUAUCAUCAACUAAAUUAAAUCAGAAAAUGAAUGAGAAAGCACCUCAAAGUACCAGGUCUAUACAGCCAUUCUCUAGAUCAAACUUACUUACAAACACACACACAACAUGUACAUAGUUUUAUUUAUUUGUUUAUUUUUCUCACAGAUGAGAUUAACAUGGGCUUUGGAGUCAUAAAGACUGAAUUUGAAUCUAAUUGCUAUCAUAUCAUAUCUCCUAUAUAGAUGGACUCUUGGGAAAGUUAAAUAAAUUUCUAAUAAUAUUACCCUUGUAGUUAGACAAUAAUACCAACUUCUUCUUAAGGUUCUUAUGAAGAUAAAUUUGUAAAAUAGCCGAACAUUUUCUGACAAGUAGUAAUUAUUGAAUAAACAUUGACCUCCUUCCCCAUGUGUUUCUAACCUCCUUUGUUAGUAAAGUUUUUUUUUUUUUUUUUUUUUUUGUCAUCCAGGCUGGAGUGCAAUGGUGCGAUCUCAGCUCACUGAAACCUCCACCUCCUGGGUUCAAGCGAUUCUCCUGCCUCAGCCUCCCAAGUAGCUGGGAUUACAGGCACCUGUCACCAUGCCUGGCUAAUUCUUGUAUUUUUAGUAGAGACAGGGUUUCACCACGUUGGCCAGGCUGGUCUUGAACUCCGGACCUCAGGUGAUCCGCCCACCUCAGCCUCCCAAAGUGCUGGUAUUACAGGCGUGAGCCACCAUGCCUGGCCAUUAGUAAGGUGUUAAAAAAUAGGUUCUCUUUGUAAAAAUUAGUUUUGAACUUUAUUUUUACUUUUUUUCUUUGCAUUCUCACCCAGUCUAUUUUUGGUCUUAUUUUGAAGUUUCGCACACCAGUCAAGAUGUAUAUAUAUGUGGGCCAUGGGAUAUACUUUCUGACUUUGUUAUUCUGUCAUGUUGACACUCUCUCAGUGGGAAUCUGCAUUGGUCUGUUUUCACACUGCUGAUAAAGACAUACCCGAGACUAGAAAGAAAAAAAGGUUUAAUUGGACUUACAGUUCCACAUGGCUAGGGAGGCCUCAGAAUCAUGGCAGGAGGCAAAAGGCACUUCUUACAUGGCAGCAGCAAGAGAAAAUGAGGAAGAAGCAAAAGCAGAAACCCCUGAUAAACCCAUCAGAUCUCCUGAGACAUAUUAACUAUCACAAGAAUAGCACGGGAAAGACCAGCCCCCAUGAUUCACAACACAUGGGAAUUCUGGGAGAUACAAUUCAAGUUGAGAUUUGGGUGGGGACACAGCCAAACCACAUCAUUCUGCCCCUGGCCCCUCCAAAUCUCAUGUCCUCACAUUUCAAACCCAGUCAUGCCUUCCCAACAGUCCCCCAAACUCAUUAACUCAUUUCAGCAUUAACCCAAAAGUCUACCAGUCCAAAGUCUCAUCUGAGACAAGGCAAGCUCCUUUUGCCUAUGAGCCUGUAAAAUAAAAAGCAAGCUGAUUACUUCCUAGAUACAAUGAGAGUACAGGUAUUGGGUAAAUACAGCUGUUCCAAAUGGGAGAAAUUGGCCAAAACAAAGGGGUUACAGGGCCCAUGCAAGUCCGAAAUCCAGUGGGACAGUCAAAUUUUAAAGCUCCAAAAUGAUCUCCUUUGAAUCCAGGUCUCAUAACCAGGUCACGCUGAUGCAAGAGGUGGGUUCCCAUGGUCUUGGGCAGCUCUGCACCUGUGGCUUUGUAGAGUAUAGCCUCCCUUCCAGCUGCUUUCAUGGGCUGGCAUUGAGUGGCUGCAGCUUUUCUAGGUGCAUGAUGCAGGUUGUCAGUGGAUCUACCAUUCUGGGGUCUGGAAGACAUUGGCCCUCUCCUCACAGCUCCAUUACAUAGUACCCAGUACGGACUCUGUGUGGGGUCUCCAACCCCACAUUUUCCAUCUGCUUUGCCCUAGCAGAGGUUCUCCGUGAGGGCCCCACCCCUGCAGAAAACUUGCCAGGGCAUCCAGGGGUUUCCAUACAUCCUCUGAAAUCUAGGCGGAGGUUCCCAAAUCUCAAUUCUUGACUUCUGUGCACCCACAGGCUCAACACUACAUGGAAGCUGCCAAGGUUUGGGGCUUCCACCCUCUGAUGCCACAGCUUGAGCUGUGUACAUUGGCCCCUUUCAGCUAUGGCUGGAGCAUCUGGGACACAGGGCACCAAGUCCCUAGGCCACACACAGCAUGGGGACCCUGGGCCCAGCACACAAAACCGCUUUUUCCUCCUGGGCCUCUGGGCCUAUGAUGGGAGGGGCUGCCACAAAGGUCUCUGACAUGGCCUGGAGACAUUUUCCUCAUGGUCUUGGGGAUUAUUAACAUUAGGCUUCUUGCUACUUAUGCAGUUUUCUGCAGCCAGCUUGAAUUUCUCCCUAGAAAAUGGGUUUUUCUUUUCUGUCGCAUAGUCAGGCUGCACAUUUUCCAUACUUGUAUGCUUUGCUUCCCUUAUAAAACUGAAUGCCUUUAACAGAACCCAAGUCACCUAAUGAAUACUUUGCUGCUUAGAAAUAUCUUCCACUAGAUACCCUAAAUCAUCCCUCUCAAGUUCAAAGUUCCACAGAUCUCUAGGGCAGGGGUAAAAUGCCGGUCUCUUUGCUAAAACAUAACAAGAGUCACCUUUACUCCAGUUUCCAACAAGUUCUUUAUCUCCAUCAGAGACCUGGACCUUAUUGUCCAUAUCGCUAUCAGCAUUUUGGGCAAAGCCACUCAACAAGUCUCUAGGAAGUUCCACACUUUCCCACAUUUUCCUGUCUUCUUCUGAGCCCUCCAAACUGUUCCAAACUCUGCCUGUUACCCAGUUCCAAAGUCACUUCUACAUUUUCUGGUAUUUUUUCAGCAACACCCCACUCCUGGUACCAGUUUACUGUGUUAGUCCAUUUUCAUGCUGCUGAUAAAGACAUACCCCAGAUUGGGAAGAAAAAAUGUUCAUUUGGACUUACAGUUCCACAUGGCUGGGGAGGCCUCAGAAUCAUGGUGGGAGGCAAAAGGCACUUCUUACAUGGUGGCAGCAAGAGAAAAUGAGGAAGAAGCAAAAGUGGAAACCCCUGAUAAACUCAUCAGAUCUUGUGAGACUUAUUAUCUGUCAGAAGAAUAGCACAGGAAAGACCAGCCGCCAUGACUCAAAUACCACCUCCUGGGUCCAUCCUGUGACACAUGGAAUUCUGGGAGAUAAAAUUCAAGUUGAGAUUUGGGUGGGGAUACAUAGCUAAACCAUAUCAGAACCUUUGUAUAUAAAAGGAACAUUGAUAGAGGAUGAUGAAAUCAUAGGAAAGACCGACAGUUUCUGAAGGACUAAUUCUAUAAAGUCUGCUGUUUAAGAGUUCUUAAUAGUAUUUUUUUAAUGAAGUGAUUUAAGUUGCAUGGUUAAUGAUCAAAACUUCUGGUAGAGGCUGGGCACGGUGGCUCACGCCUGUAAUCCCAGCAUUUUGGGAGGCUGAGGCUGGCGGAUCACAAGGUCAAGAGUUUGAGGCUAGUCUGGCCAACAUGAUGAAACCCUGGCUCUACUAAAAAUACAAAAAUUAUCUGGGCAUGGUGGCAGGCACCUAUAAUUCCAGCUACUCUGGAGUCUGAGGCAGGAUAAUCGUUUGAACCCGGGAGGCGGAGGUUGCAGCGAGCCGAGAUCACGCCAUUGCACUCCAGCCUGGGCGACAGAGUGAGACUGUGUCUCAAAAACAAACAAACAAGCAACAACAAAAACAAAAAACAAAAAAACUUCUGGUAGAGCAAUUUAUGACUUCUGGUUUUUUGUCUAGGCAGUUUAUUUUGUCUACGAUUGGAUCUAACGUACACUUUACUCCAGACCCAGGUCUAAAACCUGAUUGAUUAAAUCAGAAGUUUUUAAUGAUGCUGUAAAUGAUUUUUUAUUAUUGUUUAAUCAUAUCUUAAAAAAAACAAACGUAGGGCUGGGCACGGUGGCUCACGCCUGUAAUCCCAGCACUUUGGAAGGUUGUGGUGCGUGGAUCACCUGAGGUCAGGAGUUCAAGACCAGCCUGGCCAACAUGGUGAAACCCCAUCUCUACUAAAAAAUACAAAAAAUUAGCCAGAGGUGGUGGUGGGCGCCUGUAAUCCCAGCGACUCGGGAGGCUGAGGCAGGAGAAUCACUUGAACCCAGGAGGCAGAGAUUGCAGUAAGCUGAGAUUGCACCACUGCACUCCAGUUUGGGCAACAGAGAGAGACUCGGUCUCAAAAAAAAAAAAAAAAAAAGUAAAAACAUUGAAGUAGAAUUGGCAGGAAUGCCUUUAUUUUUUAAUCUAAAAUAUUUAAAAUGUAUUGUAGCGUAUUGAAGUGUCCUUCAGAUAAUAUCCCUUGGAACUUUUUUUUUCUCUAAUUUUGAAGUUUAGUGAUACUCUGUUUUUAUCUUAAAGUGACAUUAUCUUUCAGUAGUUCAGUGUUUGUCUCUGUCUCUCUCUCUUUUUAGCCUAUACUUCCUGGUAUAUUUGGCAGUGUAAUAAAUGUAGCUGUCAGCUAGUAUAAUUAUUCCCUUUUGUGUUUAAAUUAUUGGAGAUAGAAGAUUACAUCUGGAUAUUAGUCUCUUCAUUCAGUAUUGACAAGUGAUGGUAUCCAGUGGUACUUAAAUCAUUGGAUGAUGGAAAACAUCUUUUUCUUCCAUUAGGAAAGAAUUUUACAUGGACUUAAAAAUCAAAGUAUUUAAUGUGUAUAUCUAGUACAUGUUUUAUACACUGUGCUUAGAUCCUUUGGGUUGAAUUUUUGUUUGAAUAGAAAAAAAUUUUGUUUGGAUAGAACAAAAAAUACAUUUAAAACAUUGCUCUAAGUUUCAGGAUAAGCAUUUUAUUUUUCAGGGAGCACUCUUUAGUAAAUAUUAUAUGAGUGUAUUAAUGGUACUCUGAUAAGGUAGAAAUAAUUAUUUAAGGAGAAUUCAGAUUAAAAACUGGAGAGUAAUUGUUUUAUAACAUUAGAACCCUGAAUGGCAAUUUGAUGAACUGGAGAAGAAAAAGAUGUCUGCAAUAAAUCAGAAACAAACCCUUCAGCUUCAGCAGUAGUGCUCAUUAUUUUUUUUAAAAAAAUAGAGCCUCUAGGAUCAAACAUAUUAUACAAAGUAGCAUGUAUCAUUAAAAGUAUAAAUUGGUAUCCUUUUUAAGGGGAGUAUAAAGAAGUAUGUAGGAGUCAGUGUGGUCUGAAAAAUGGAAAGGUUAUUUUGCUGCUAAAAUAUAGGUUUUUUUACAGUGUAAGUGCAUUGCUCAGAACAUAUCUUCUUCCACGCUUCAAAAGAGUUUGGGUAAGGGAACAGCCUGAAAAACACCUGAAAGAGAGAAUUCUGGCUUAUGGAUUAGAGAGCAUCUAUAAACAGAACAAAUUGGUGAAUAAGAGUUCACAAAAAUUUUGUCUAAGAAAUUUCCCCACAUGCAUUCAGAGGUUAAUAAUUAAAUUUUUUGAAGUUCAUUUUAAAACAUUGCUUAUUUUAACAUGUAAACGUAUGUUGGGUGGGAAAAGUACAAAUGGGAGAUUGAAACUGUUUUAAUCAUGUAAAUGAUCAGCCCUACAAUUUUUGUUUUUUUAAUAAUCUGGAAUGCUUAUUUUAUAUGCUGGGAUGCUAGUUGUUUUUUCUAUUAAUACACUUAACUUGCAUUCUAGCUUCGCCAUUCAGAGACAGGCAUCGUGUGGUGGGUUGUGUGACAGUGUCUGUCAAUAGUGAAGACAAAUAGUGCCAGAGACACUUAACCCAUCCAAUCUCACCCAGGGUAUAGGUCGGUCUCGUUUUCAGACUUCUUCAUAAGUCCUUCUUUCUUUCUCUCUUCCUUUCUUACUUUUUGUUUGUUUGUUUCUAAAUAGUGGAUUGAUACUGAUUGAAACUAAAACUUUUUGUAAAGUUUUAAACUUUGCAUUAAUAUUAUAAGAAAAAGAAGAAAAGUAGAAAAUGAAGGUUGGCAUGUAAGGUGUCGACAAAGCAGGUUUGCAGCCACUUUGUGUGUUCUAGAUAUUUCAAUCUCUUGGCAACAUGAGUGUUGGCCUUACAGCUUUUUUCUCUGAAUAUCUUUCUUCUUUAAUCUGAAAAUAUGUCCUUGUAUCUGGUGACUUUUAUCAGAUGAGAACUUCAGAGUUGGUCAUUGUUACCAGUAAGAAAAAUAUAAUGCUUAAGAAGAAAUAACGAAGGUUGAACAUUAUGUGUUUUAGAUCAGAAAUAGUUUCUGGCCAGGCACAGUGGUUCACGCCUGUAAUCCCAGCACUAUGGGAGGCUGAGGCAGGCGGAUCAGCUGAGGUCAGGAGUUCGAGACCAGCCUGACCAACAUGGUGAAACCCUGUCUCUACUAAAAAUACAGAAUUAGCCGGGCGUGGUGGUGCAUGCCUGUAAUCCCAGCUACUUGGGUGGCUGAGGCAGAAGAAUCGCUUGACUCUGGGAGGUAGAGGUUGCAGUGAGCCAAAAUCGUGCCAUUGUACUCCAGCGGGGGCAACAGGAGCGAAACUCCAUCUCAAAAGAAAAAAAAAAAGGCCGGGCACGGUGGCUCACACCUGUAAUCCCAGCACUUUGAGAGGCCAAAGUGGGCAGAACACAAGGUCAGGAAUUUGAGACCAGCCUGGCCAAUACGGUGAAACCCCGUCUCUACUAAAAAUACAAAAAUUAGCCAGGUGUGGUGGCGGGCACCUGUAGUCCCAGCUACUCGGGAGGCUGAGGCAGGAGAAUCGCUUUUACCUGGGAGGCAGAGGUUGCAGUGAGCCAAGAUUGUGCCACUGCAUUCCAGCCUGGGCAACAGAGUGAGACUCCGUCUCAAAAAAAAAAAAAAAAAAAAAAAGGAAAUUGUUUCCAAAUAUCUUUUUUUUAAUGAUUAUUUUUGAAUAGUCAAUAAUUUAUUCCUUCUUUGUUCCACUAUUUGUUCACUUAGCACUCUUGCAAAAUUUUAUGGCUUUUUUUAAACUAGCUUUUUUAGAAAACUCAAUUUUGCACAGAUGUUGAAAAAUUAUAAAAUAUGUACAUAUUCAAAUGUUAGGGAUCAAAUUUUAAUCUUGGAAGCUUGGAAAUUAAAUAUCAUUUCUGUCAUAUAUUUUAAAGCAGUGAAAGGUAUUUCUUUCUUUUGAGGACUUCAGCAAAUAUUUCUAAUUUCAAAGCUUUCUAUUAAAAGUUUUUAGUUCCAUAUAAAGUAUAUCUUUUUUAUGAUAUUUUAAGCACUAAUAUAUUAUGGUAGUUAAAAUAAUUUCUAGUUGACAAAUCUAGAGCUGAUAGUUCUUAAGUUUAAAAUACAGUUUAAGCAAGGAGUAUAUAAAAUCUACAUGGGUUUCUAUAAAUGGUAUCGUUUAAAAUCUUAUUUCAGUCUGGGCAUGGUGCCUCAUGCCUGUAAUCCUAGCACUUUGGGAGGCUGAGGUGGGAGAAUCCCUUGAGCCUAGGAGUUCAAAACCAGCCUGGGCAACAUGGUGAAACCCUAUCUCUACAAAAAAAUACAAAAAUUAGCCAGGUAUGGUGGUGCAUACCUGUAGUCCUAGCUAUUCAGGAGGCUGAGGUGGGAUGAUCGCUUGAGCCCAGGAGGUCGAGGCUGCAGUGGGUUGUGAUCGUGCCCCUACACUCCAGCCUGGGCAACAGAGCAAGACUGUCUCAACAAAGAAAACAAAAAAGAAAGUAAAGAAAGUAAAUAAAAUCCUGUUUCAUCUUUUAUUAAAUUGCAGAUUCUGGGAUAUUCAUAUUCCAUGUAGACAUUAUUUAAUAUCUGCCAGUCUUUGAAUCUCAACUAUUUUUGAGUAUUUAUAGUUUCCAUCAAUUCUUAAAAGAAGCUGUAUGUACAAUUCAAGUUCACCAUCGUUACUGGCAUUUGGUCUGAUAACUGGCUACUGUUAAUAGUGGCAAACAGACUUAAAUACAGGAUACUUUACAUAUGACACUUUACCUGCCUCUUUUAAAUUUUAAAAUUAUUCUAUUUAAAAUAAUCUGACAUUAUAAAUUUCUAUGAGUAAAUUAUAGAAUGGUCUAUUAAUUUUUCCUUUAGUUUGUUGUGCUUUCUGUGGUCACAGAAAAUGCUUUAGAAAAAAUAAAAUUAUUCUAGCCCAGGCACAGUGGCUCAUACCUGUAAUCCCAGCACUUUGGGAGGCUGAGGUGGGCAGAACACAAGGUCAGGAGUUCAAGACCAGCCUGGCCAGUAUGGUGAAACUAUCUCUACUAAAAAUACAAAAAUUAGCCGGACGUGGUGGCGGGUGCCUGUAGUCCCAGCUACUCGGGAGGCUAAGGCAGGAGAAUCGUUUGAACCCGGGAGGUGGAGGUUGCAGAGAGCCAAGAUUGUGCCACUGUACUCUAGCCUUGGCAACAGAGCAAGACUGUGUCUCAAAAAAAAGAAAAGAAAAGAAAAGAAAAAGGAAAAAAAAAGUAUUCUAUAUAAGUUAGACUAUAGGUUCAAAGAUAAUUCCUUCAUAAAAGAAAAAAAAUCAAUAAAAUUUAUUCACAUGGCCAUGCACCAUGGCUCACGCCUGUAAUCUCAGCACGUCAGGAGGCCGAGGUGGGUGGAUCACUUGAAGUCAGGAGUUCGAGACCACCCUGGCCAACAUGAUGAAAUCCCAUCUCUACUAAAAUACAGAAAUUAGCUGGGCGUGGUGGUAGGCACCUGUAAUCCCAGCUACUCAGGAGGCUAAGGCGGGAGAAUCACUUGAAACCUGGGAGGCAGAGGUUCCAGUGAGCCGAGAUCGCGCCACUGCACUCCAGCCUGGGCAACAGAGCGAGAGUCCCUCUCAAAAAAAAAAAAAAAAAAGAAUAUAUAGACGGGUCAGAACUGCAUUCACACUUUGGUUCUAUAGAAUAUCAAGCUGUUUUUUGAUACUUUAUUUAGUGAUACAGUGGUAUUCCCAGGAGGAUUUGUCAGCACUUUUCUGGGAAUGCUUGGAAAUGACUAAUUAGCAUUAGAAAUUUAAAAUGUUCUGAUAUCAUUAUUUUAUGUAUUUAUAUUUUAAUAGGAUAUUAAGGAUUUUUUUCAUGGUAAAUUUAUGGAUAUAUAAGUAGGUAAUUUGGCUUACUUAUAAUUUAAGGAAAUAAAAUUACUAGAGUACUCUCGGUAGAGAUAGCAAAUCGUUACCUCUAGACUCUUAGUAUUUUCUCUGUAUCAAAUAAUGCUAUCGUAGUAAUAUAUAUUCUAAGUACUUUGAAUUAUAUUUGAAUUAUAUUUGAAUAUAAAAGAAUAAAAAUUCUUUUAUUCUUCAACCUACAUUUAUUUGCCAGCUUAUCUUUAAUGUAACUCCAAAUACAUACCAAAUUUUUGGCUUCCCAGAAAUCAAUUUAAUAAUUUGAAUUUUAUUACAAUGUAGGCACUGUGAUAGGUGUUGGGAGGAUCUAAGAUGAGAAAGAUAUUGUCAGUGCUUUCGAAGUGCUCACAGUUCUUACCCUCCAUUUUACUACCUCACAUGGCAUUAUUAAUUAAUGCACUCAGAUCUCUUGCUAACCAGAAUGUAAUGUUUUGAUGUGAAAGAUUUUAUACAUCAUUAUCAUCAUCAGAGGAUCAAUAGUACCAUGGUAAAGAAUUUUAGGCUGGGUGUGGUGGCUCACGCUUAUAAUCCCAGUACUUUGGGAGGCCAAAGCUGGAGGAUUGCUUGAGCCCAAGAAUUUGAGACCACCUGGGCAGCAUGACAAAACUUUGCCUCUACAAAUAAUUUAAAAAGUAGCCAGGCAUGGUGUUGUGUGCCUGUAGUCUCAGUUACUCGGGAAGCUGAGGCAGGAGGAUUGCUUGAGCCCAGGAGAUCAAGGCUGCAGUGAGCCAUGAUCGUGCCACUGCACUGUAGCCUGGGCAACAGAGUGAGACCCUGCCUCAAAAAAAAAAAAGAAUUUUACAGUUUAAAAAAAAUUAUUUCAUUUGUCUUAAAAUGAGUAGAAUCUUUGCAAUUGAGGUAGACUUUAAAAAGUAAUAUUUUUCUAUUAAAAGAUGGUUACUGUUCUUUUCUGACAGAGUUAAUAUUUUCAGUGUCAUAGUUUUGUGCUAACUUUUUCUUUAAUAAGUAUGCCCAGGAUCAAUCCUGCAGUUGUGCACACACAAUCGUGUGUUAGCUGUCCAUGGAAAAUGUAUAGAAUAUUUAAAUUUAUGUAGGAUAUGAUAUCACAGUUUGGCAUACUUACCCUAGAACACACACUUAUGUCUGACUGUUAAAUCAGUUGGGUUUUAUAAUCAUUACGGUUUUGAUAUUUGAUAAGAUUUGCAAGAUAAAAUUUUUUACCUCAGAGAACAAGACAAGGUUAUAUCGUGCAUAUUAAAUUCAUAAUACCAUAUAACUUGCUUUUGGGUUCAUGAUUGCUUUUCACCUGUACUUUCCAUCUGUCAUGAACAGGGAUCCCUGAGAUGUUCAUACUCUGCAUUCUCAUGUGCAUGAUCCUUAGAUUUAAAAAGGGAUUUGCCUCUGAAGCAGGGAGUGUCUGCAUUAAAAAUGACCUGUAGUUCUCUGCUUCAUAGGUUAGAAACUUAUUUUAAUAUUUUGUGGCUAAGCACAGUCCCACUUUUCAAAUUCUAUAAUGAAUUAUUUAAUUGGCAUUGAAUGUGGACCACCAGCAUAUAUUUCAUAUUGGGGUUUUCUUUAUUACUUUAAAUGAUUAAAAUUCAAUAGAAUGUCCAGCUGAGGCAAUAAAAGCUUUAUUUUUGCUUUACAGCUUAAAACGUUAAAUGAGAUUUUAAAAAUCUAUGGAUUGUAACAUAAGUAAAAUAAUGCUAUUUGGGCAUUUUUAAAAAUUCCAUUUCUUAGGCCUUAUAUUGCUUGAAGCAUUUAUAUUCUAAAACAUAACCAAAUUCUGACUAUUCAUUUUGGGGAAAAACAAUCAGUUCACAAAUCACAUUUUCAAUGGGACUGCUAGCCAGCAUAGGUGAAAACAUGUAUAGUGUAUUUACUCUUGAAUUGUACACUGCAGAUGCUUCUUCAGCUCCCUCCUCUUCCUCCAUGGGCGGUGCUUGCAGCUCCUUUACCACCUCUUCCAGCCCUACCAUUUAUUCUACCUCAGUCACCGACAGCAAGGCUAUGCAAGUGGAGAGCUGCUCCUCAGCCGUGGGGGUAAGUAACAGAGGGGUAAGUGAAAAGCAGUUAACCAGUAACACAGUUCAGCAGCAUCCAUCAACACCGAAGAGGCACACAGUCUUGUACAUCUCACCACCACCUGAGGACUUGCUGGAUAACAGUCGGAUGUCCUGCCAGGAUGAGGGGUGUGGAUUGGAAUCUGAGCAGAGCUGCAGUAUGUGGAUGGAGGAUUCCCCCUCCAACUUCAGUAACAUGAGCACCAGUUCCUACAAUGAUAACACUGAGGUACCUCGUAAAUCACGAAAACGAAAUCCAAAGCAGAGGCCGGGGGUCAAACGACGAGAUUGUGAAGAAUCUAAUAUGGAUAUAUUUGAUGCCGACAGUGCCAAAGCACCUCACUAUGUGCUUUCUCAGCUUACCACGGACAACAAAGGCAACUCAAAAGCGGGAAAUGGAACAUUGGAAAACCAAAAAGGAACUGGAGUAAAGAAGAGCCCUAUGUUGUGUGGACAAUAUCCUGUUAAAAGUGAGGGAAAGGAGCUGAAGAUAGUUGUACAACCUGAGACACAGCACCGAGCUCGGUACCUGACUGAGGGCAGCCGUGGCUCAGUGAAAGAUAGAACACAGCAAGGCUUUCCUACAGUAAAGCUGGAAGGCCAUAAUGAACCUGUAGUGUUGCAAGUGUUUGUGGGCAACGACUCUGGACGAGUGAAACCACAUGGAUUUUAUCAGGCCUGCAGAGUAACUGGACGAAAUACAACUCCUUGCAAAGAAGUGGACAUUGAAGGCACUACUGUUAUAGAAGUCGGCCUUGAUCCUAGCAACAACAUGACACUGGCGGUGGACUGCGUAGGGAUAUUGAAAUUGAGGAAUGCUGAUGUCGAAGCCAGAAUAGGAAUUGCUGGUUCCAAGAAGAAAAGCACUCGUGCCAGAUUGGUUUUUCGAGUUAAUAUCAUGAGGAAAGAUGGCUCCACUUUGACACUGCAAACACCCUCUUCUCCAAUUUUGUGUACUCAGCCAGCAGGAGUGCCAGAAAUCUUAAAGAAAAGCUUGCAUAGCUGUUCAGUGAAAGGAGAAGAAGAAGUGUUUUUAAUCGGCAAGAACUUUCUGAAAGGAACUAAAGUUAUUUUCCAAGAAAAUGUUUCUGAUGAAAACUCUUGGAAGUCAGAAGCUGAAAUUGAUAUGGAACUAUUUCAUCAGAAUCAUCUUAUUGUGAAGGUUCCUCCCUAUCAUGACCAACAUAUAACUUUGCCUGUGUCAGUGGGAAUAUAUGUAGUGACAAAUGCUGGAAGAUCUCAUGAUGUUCAACCAUUCACUUACACUCCAGACCCAGCAGCAGCUGGUGCUUUGAAUGUAAAUGUGAAGAAGGAAAUAUCUAGUCCAGCAAGACCUUGCUCUUUUGAAGAGGCCAUGAAAGCAAUGAAAACUACUGGAUGUAAUUUAGAUAAGGUAAAUAUUAUCCCUAAUGCCCUGAUGACUCCACUCAUACCAAGCAGUAUGAUUAAGAGUGAAGAUGUUACUCCAAUGGAAGUAACAGCAGAAAAAAGAUCUUCCACUAUUUUUAAGACUACAAAGUCUGUUGGAUCAACUCAGCAAACAUUAGAAAACAUCUCAAACAUAGCAGGAAAUGGCUCUUUUUCAUCACCAUCAUCUUCCCACCUACCUUCUGAAAAUGAAAAACAGCAGCAGAUUCAGCCCAAGGCAUACAACCCAGAGACCCUGACAACUAUUCAAACCCAGGACAUCUCACAGCCUGGUACUUUUCCAGCAGUUUCUGCUUCUAGUCAGCUGCCCAACAGCGAUGCACUAUUGCAGCAGGCUACACAGUUUCAGACAAGAGAAACUCAGUCUAGAGAGAUAUUACAGUCAGAUGGUACAGUGGUUAAUUUGUCACAACUGACUGAGGCAUCACAACAACAGCAGCAGUCACCACUACAAGAACAAGCACAGACUUUACAGCAGCAGAUUUCAUCAAAUAUUUUUCCAUCACCAAAUAGUGUGAGUCAGCUUCAGAAUACUAUUCAGCAGCUGCAAGCAGGGAGUUUCACAGGCAGUACUGCUAGUGGCAGCAGUGGAAGUGUUGACUUGGUCCAACAAGUUUUAGAGGCACAGCAGCAGUUAUCUUCAGUUUUAUUUUCUGCUCCAGAUGGUAAUGAGAAUGUUCAAGAGCAGCUUAGUGCAGAUAUUUUUCAACAAGUCAGUCAAAUUCAGAGUGGUGUAAGCCCUGGAAUGUUUUCCUCAACAGAGCCAACAGUCCAUACCAGACCAGAUAAUUUAUUACCUGGAAGAGCUGAAAGUGUUCAUCCACAGUCUGAAAACACGUUAUCUAAUCAACAGCAGCAGCAGCAGCAGCAACAGCAAGUGAUGGAAUCUUCAGCCGCAAUGGUGAUGGAGAUGCAACAGAGUAUCUGCCAGGCAGCUGCCCAGAUUCAGUCAGAGUUAUUCCCUUCAACUGCUUCAGCAAAUGGAAACCUUCAGCAAUCGCCAGUUUACCAGCAGACUUCUCACAUGAUGAGUGCAUUGUCUACCAAUGAGGAUAUGCAAAUGCAGUGUGAAUUGUUUUCUUCUCCUCCUGCAGUUUCUGGAAAUGAAACUUCUACAACUACCACACAGCAGGUUGCAACCCCUGGCACUACCAUGUUUCAGACAUCAAGUUCAGGAGAUGGAGAAGAAACUGGAACACAAGCAAAACAGAUUCAGAACAGUGUCUUUCAGACCAUGGUCCAAAUGCAACAUAGUGGGGACAAUCAACCUCAAGUUAACCUUUUUUCAUCCACAAAAAGUAUGAUGAGUGUUCAGAAUAGUGGUACCCAACAACAAGGUAAUGGUUUAUUCCAGCAAGGGAAUGAGAUGAUGUCACUUCAAUCUGGAAAUUUUUUGCAGCAGUCUUCUCAUUCACAGGCCCAACUUUUUCAUCCUCAAAAUCCUAUUGCCGAUGCUCAGAACCUUUCCCAGGAAACUCAAGGUUCUCUCUUUCAUAGUCCAAAUCCUAUUGUCCACAGUCAGACUUCUACAACCUCCUCUGAACAAAUGCAGCCUCCAAUGUUUCACUCUCAAAGUACCAUUGCUGUGUUACAGGGCUCUUCAGUUCCUCAAGACCAGCAGUCAACCAACAUAUUUCUUUCCCAGAGUCCCAUGAAUAAUCUUCAGACUAACACAGUAGCCCAAGAAGCAUUUUUUGCAGCACCGAACUCAAUUUCUCCACUUCAGUCAACAUCAAACAGUGAACAACAAGCUGCUUUCCAACAGCAAGCUCCAAUAUCACACAUCCAGACUCCUAUGCUUUCCCAAGAACAGGCACAACCCCCGCAGCAGGGUUUAUUUCAGCCUCAGGUGGCCCUGGGCUCCCUUCCACCUAAUCCAAUGCCUCAAAGCCAACAAGGAACCAUGUUCCAGUCACAGCACUCAAUAGUUGCCAUGCAGAGUAACUCUCCAUCCCAGGAACAGCAGCAGCAGCAGCAACAGCAGCAGCAACAGCAGCAGCAACAACAACAGAGCAUUUUAUUCAGUAAUCAGAAUACCAUGGCUACAAUGGCGUCUCCAAAGCAACCACCACCAAACAUGAUAUUCAACCCAAAUCAAAAUCCAAUGGCUAAUCAGGAGCAACAGAACCAGUCAAUUUUUCACCAACAAAGUAACAUGGCCCCAAUGAAUCAAGAGCAACAGCCCAUGCAAUUUCAGAGUCAGUCCACAGUUUCCUCACUUCAGAACCCAGGUCCUACCCAGUCGGAAUCAUCACAGACCCCCUUGUUCCAUAGCUCUCCUCAGAUUCAGUUGGUACAAGGGUCACCUAGUUCUCAAGAGCAGCAAGUAACUCUCUUCUUAUCUCCAGCAUCCAUGUCUGCCUUGCAGACCAGUAUAAAUCAACAAGAUAUGCAACAGUCUCCUCUUUAUUCCCCUCAGAACAACAUGCCUGGAAUUCAAGGAGCCACAUCUUCGCCUCAACCACAGGCUACUUUAUUUCACAACACAGCAGGAGGCACAAUGAACCAACUGCAGAAUUCUCCUGGCUCAUCUCAGCAGACAUCAGGAAUGUUCUUAUUUGGCAUUCAAAAUAACUGUAGUCAGCUUUUAACCUCUGGACCAGCUACAUUGCCUGAUCAGUUGAUGGCCAUAAGUCAGCCAGGCCAACCACAAAACGAGGGCCAGCCACCUGUGACAACACUUCUUUCUCAGCAAAUGCCAGAGAAUUCUCCACUGGCAUCCUCUAUAAACACCAACCAGAACAUCGAAAAGAUUGAUUUGCUUGUUUCAUUGCAAAACCAAGGGAACAACUUGACUGGCUCCUUUUAACUGGAUAUAAAUUCCACGAAGAAAAUCCUGAUUCCAAGAUGUCCUGAGAUCUUGUGGUUCCAUGAGAAUUAUUACUUUAAAAACAAAACAAAAUAUAAAAAACUGUGUUUGAGUAAACUGAUAGAUUUUACUCUGACUGCAAAAGAGCACACCUAUGCUGCUUGUUGCAGUAACUAACCACCAAUGUUAACAUCUUCAUAUUUUAUAUUCCUAAUAACAGUGAUGACUGAGAAUCUAUUUGAGUUUCCAGCUGGCAGAAUUAAUUGUUAUUAUUUUCCUAGGCGCAAUUUCCUUAAACGUACAGUUUAAAUUCAAGGCUGGACCACUCAGUUAUUAUUGCUAUUAGAAAAUAAUAUAUCAUGUUUACUUUUGUUCUUCAUUAUUUUCUUUCCUGCAUUGUUUUAGUCAAGUAAUGGCUUUUGAAAAAGUAAAGUUCAAUAAUAACUAAGGCUGUGAUUUUUUUCAAUAUAAAAGGCACAGCUGUUGGCCAAAGUGAAGGAAUCUUUUUUCAGUUUUAUUGGAGAAACUGAAGGGUAACAUUCUAACAAGUAAACUGUAUGUGCAGAUAAAAGUACUCUUGAUUUAACACAAAGGCAGAUGAUACACUUAUAAAACUGGGAACAGCUGGAAUGCUUCUUGAUUUUAUUUUUUCAGAGAGUUGUUAGUUCUCUGGGUUUCUACUAAGGGGUUUAGCCAUAACUGUGCAUAGAAAAAUAAUUAUCUGUAAAAAAUGAAGGGGAUAAUAUAUGAUAAAUUAUGUUCUGAUAUCCUCCUACAGUAGUUUAAAUUGACAGAAAAAUUUGAAUGUUUUCUUCUUAACCCAGUCUUAGGCUGGUAUUCCCUUUUUAUAUAUAUCUAUAUUACUUUUCACCUCUUUUUCACUUUACUUUAGAGAACUAUUAAUAUACUACUGGCUUCAUGACCCUGUAGCAUCUUUGGCCACUUUAAUCUAGGGUGACCUAGCAAUCCUGCAGCACAGGGCAGAGAGUACUGUCUUAGGAAUUAUUAGGAGUUGAUUCCUGAGAAACAACACAUUUUUCCCCAUGAACGGUGCUGUUCUGAAGUCUUCAAAUUUUUCCCUCUAAUAGGAAACAGUAUAAAUUUUAAUUAAAAAAAAAAGGCAAACUAAAAUUUCUUGAAAUAUCACUUCUCCCUGAUCUGCAGUGAGUAUAAAUUCACUUGUCACCUCAGUGCUUUACAGUUUGAAGUGGUCACUUACCUGAUGGUUCCCACAAGCCUUAGGCUUUACAGGGUUGUAUCAUUGACUUAAAAUGAAGAAUUAACUUGUGUUACAUCUAUAAAGAGCAAAAUAACACACUCCAGAACUUGGCAGUUGUAGCAUUAGUUAUACAGUUUUGGGUGUUCUUGCCACCCGUGGGAUGCCUGCUUCUCACUACCACCUGUGUCUGGACACAUGCUUAUGUCUCAUUUUCCUUUUGGCAUGUGGAAAGCUGUCAAUGCAGUGUAAGGCCAACGUGUGUGUGGCUUCUAUGUGUUGAGAUAAUGUUUUGGUAUCCUUGUCCGUUUCAUUUAUUUUUUAAGUGUACAAAAAAUAACCUGUUAAUUGUUGAAGGCUACUUUUCUGUUCUUUUUUUUUUUUUUUUUCUAUCCUGUACAUUUAGUUGAACUGUGCGGAAUUGUGGUGUUGGUUUUGUUUACACAGCCAGAUUUUUCCUUCUUUUUGUUUUGUGAUGAUCUUCCUUUGUUCUUUGAAUGUGCUCUUUUGUCUUUUUCUCUUUUUUCUCAUGUUUUCUUCCCUCCACCUCCACCCCUUUCUUUCUUUCUCUCUCUGAUUGAGAGGCAUUGAAUUACGUUUUCAGUAGUACAGGCUUCUUGCCGAUAUGAAGGGAACUUUUCAGAAAGAGACCUACUCUGGGUCAUUUAAUUUUGAAUACAGUUUUCAAUCGUUCAAGUUUUGGAUGGUUUAUAUCUAAUGUGUGUUUCAUUUUUUUGGAAAGCUAUAUUUUGUAUUUAGGAAAUGGUAUACUAUUUUGCUAUUUGUACUGAGUGAGUACAUUGGCAUAAAUAUAGAAAUUUAUAUAUAUACAUAUAUAUAAACUAUUCUUUUUUGCCACACAUUUUUGUGGUAAAUUUGUGAGUUUGUCUGAUGUUCUACCACAACGUGGCGUCUGAUAACAGUGAGGGGGGGUGGGGUUUGUUAUGUCUUUAUUGAGUAUUUAAGUAUCUUUUGAAACAAAUGACCUGUUCAUCUGUGGCCAUUCCAUCAGGCAGUUAGUUCCUUGAUGUCAGUAGUGGGCUAAAGGCAGCUUACUGUGUGUUUGCUGGAGCUUUCACUCAGCCAAGUGUUAGAGUCAGGAAACCCAUUGAGGCAAUGGCGUCAAAUGGUGUUUCACAAGAAUGAGCCAUUCAGUCUUUGCUCACUAUAUAUUUAAUAUUUUAUUAUUGUUGUUAUUGUUAUUAUUAAUUGGCUUUCUGUAUUCUAUGCCUUUUAUUUAUAAAGACACUAAGAAAACCCAUGUUUGUAAUUUUAAUAACAUUUUUCCCAUCUUGUAAUAUCCAGAGCUACUUUAUAAAUUCUCUGAACCAAAAGUAUUUUCCUCAGUGUAUCUCUUCUCCCCCAGCCCCUAUUGGGAAAAAUUACCCAGUAUAGUUCAGGUUAUGAGGAGGAUCAGCCACACAAUCCAGUGCUUCAGUUUGAAAAUGUAAAAUUCUAACCCUAAAGUAGGGUUGGUUGAAAUUUCAGACAAAGCAAACCCAGCAGGUAUAAAAAGUAGUAUAAAUACAAAUCUGUAAGUUAUUUUUGAAUUUUCUGAACUUUUUUCUAAGAGAUUACAUAGGAGACUAAAGAAAUCUAUCUGUUCAAGUUCUAAUUAGGAUGAUUGUUAAUACUGCACUGUGGAUGAAGUGGCGACUGGCUUGUGUGCUGACUUCUGUGGUUUAGCAAGAGGUUUAUUGUUAUCAAAUGCUAAUUGGCAAUGCCAAGUCACUGGGACCAAUUUUCUGUUUUAUAAUAUCUAAGUUUAGAACAGAAUAUAUACCUGAACUGUAGUGGUUUGAUCGGAUGGAGACAGAAAACCCGAUUUUUAUUCUCAUAAAUUUUGUGGUUAUUUAUACAAGGGCUGUGCUAUGCUACCAUAUUCUUGUUCAAUAAUAAUAGGUUUGUUGUUUUUUUUACAUUGUUAAAUGUUCCUUACCCCUAAAGGUCAAUGUUAAGUACAACAUUCUGAAAAUACAAUUUGGCUACGAAGAGUAUUCAUCUUCUUUGAAGCUCAGUGGUUGAUAUUUGUGCUAAUAAUGCAAUUUCCUGAUUACUGUUACAAGUUAUAGCUACAUAUGGGAGAGACUCAGUGAGCCAGCAAAGGCCAUAGAAACAACAAUUUAUUAAAUGUAUUUAUGGCAGAAGGACCUAAAUAAACUGUGAGCCACCUUUUCUUCUUUAUAUUGUUACAUUUAAGUGUUCUUGCUUUCAGCAACUCACAUUAAUGCUUGGAGCUUAUCUCUUUCUCUCUCUCUCUCUCUCUCUCUGUGUGUGUGUGUGUAUGUGUGUGUGUGUGUGUGUGUGUUUCCUUAUUGUCAUUCCAUUAUAUAUCCACACCAACAUGGGUGACGAUAAUUCAAAGUCAUAUUUUGCCUCUAAGCUUGAUCAUGUUACCUUUAUGAUUAAAGUAUCAUGUUAUUUAGCCAAUGCAAAUCUGUUUUAAAACAAAUAGUUUAAAAAAAGAACAAGUUUUUAAGGGCUUUAUUAUAGAAGAAGUAUUAAUGAAGGACUUUCCUUCCUCCCUCCCUUUCCUCCCCUCCCUGCCUCCCUUCUUCCCUUCCAUCUCCCCCUCCUCCCUGCCUUCUUUGUUUCUCCUUCCCUUAUUCCUCCCUCCCUCCUUUCUCCCUUCCUUCCUUUCUUCCAUUCAUCCUUCCUUGCCUUUUAUUUUUAUUUUUUGUAAUAUCACAUGUGCUGUAGUUUGGAAUUUUAUUCUAGUGCAUUUCUUGCUCAUCAGAACCUCAGCUAAUCUACCUAGGAAAAAUAGUAUCAAAGGAAAUGAGAAAGUUGUAUCUGAGUCCCUCCAGAACUAAGAUAAUUCUUUUUGACCAUUUAAGCCUUUAUAAAUGCGUUUUGACCAUUUAAGCCUUUAUAAAUGCUUGUUUUAGGAAAGUGAAUCUGUUAGAUGCAUCAACAAAUAAUGACCAGGACAAAACGAUUUAAUAAUUAAAGUCUCAAAUCACCAUGGUUAUACAUUUUCACCAGAAAUAGUAAUCUUACAAUUUUUCAUUUUUCUGAUGAAGAUUUCUGUUCCAAUAUCUGUUUCCUAAUAGAUUUUUUAAAUUAAUUAGCUUUCCUCUGCUUUAUGACCACAGGUUUUAUCCCUAACCGAGACAGCUGUCUUAUAUCUGCAUGCCUUAGACUGUGUGGAGGGACUCCAUGAAGAAAGACCAUAGGUUAGAAAAAUAACUCAUAGUAUAUACCCUAGUAAGUGGGUUAGUAGAAUCUCAUAACAUGUAUUAAAAAGAGGUUUUCUUCUCUGCUUGUUUGUGUCACUAGAGCAAAAUUGUAGAGAUAAUGCUCAUAAUGCAGUAAAUAUCAGAAUAAUAUCUACAAUAUCAUUUGUGGAUGGUCCCAGGUCCCAGUGCUCUAGUUACUUUACUUCUUUUUUUUUUUUUGAGAUGGAGUCUUGCUCUGUCUCUCAGGCUAGAGCAGUGUGCGAUCUCAGCUCACUGCAGCCUCCACCUCCCAGGUUCAAGCGAUUCUCCUGCCUCAGCCUCCCAAGUAGCCAGGAUUACAGGCACCCUCCACUAGGCCCGGCUAAUUUUUUUUGUAUUUUUUUAGUAGAGAUGGGGUUUUGCCAUGUUGGCCAGGCUGGUUUCGAACUCCUAACCUCCAGUGAUCCACCUGCCUCGGCGUCCCAAAGUGCUAGGAUUACAGGCAUGAGCCACCACAUCCGGCCUAAUUACUUCUUUAAUCCCCAUUUAUUUUUAUGCCAUUCUAGCCUCAUUUAUUAAUAAAAUUAUGUUUUUACUUUCUCUUUCAGGAAAUUUUUUAAAUUAAUAUUUUAUAUCUAGAUCUAAUGCUAUGGAAAAGUGCCUUUUUAUCAUUUAUAAUUUCAUUUUUCACUAUUUCCAAAAACACAUAAACAAAUAGUUUCAGUAGGUCCCAGCUUUUACUUUUUCCAUUUAAACCUUCUUUUCUCCAUUUCUUCCCUUUGGCUUAAGAAUAAAAGAAAAGGUACAUUGCUAGAAUUGUUUCUUUGGGAGAGGGUAAAAGAUUACAGAAUUAGACUGUUCAGCCUUUAUAUAAACUAAAUUUGUCUUCAUCUCAACCAGCUAAUGGUAGGUCUUAUCUGAAUACUCAUGAGAAUUUUAGCAUCUGUGAAACUCCAUGCACCAGAUGUGUGUAAAUUUCAGGAAGAAAGUGUUGAAAGCAUUUUCUCUGAUGUUAAUUAGAUGGAAAUAAAUCACUAAAACAUAGUUUAGGUAAAGCCUGAUUAUGCCACUUUUUUUUAACUAGACAGGGCAAAGUUGUUUAUGUUAGUGUACUUCUUGUCUAUCCUCAGUUAAUUUACCUAGACAAAAAGUGUCAAAGGAAAUGAGAAAAAGGUUAUAUCUGACUCCCUCCAGACCUAAGAUAAUUCCUUUUGAUCAGAUACAGUCAGAUGGAGUGCCUUGGUUUUUGUUAAUUUUGCCUCUAUUCCAGCUCCUUACCACAGCGGUGGUGCUUAAAGAAAGGAUCAUCAGCAACAGGUCAGGAUAGUUCUACCUUUGGGAUAGGGCUGCUUUCCCCGUGCUAGUAUUUCUGUGACUGUUAGUGGCACUGAGGACUGCAAACUUUUAUGCAAUAUUCUUAAUACCCUAUUGAUAUUAUGCACUUUAAUCAUUCCAAAGAAGCCAAGAAUGCUGUAUAGUGAUGAUUCCUUCCUAAUGAAUUCAUCUUAACUAUUUAGAAUGUUAUGUCCCUUUUCUUUUGGAUAGCCAACUUGGUAUAAAUGUUAUAUGGAUUUUUCUAAAAUGACUAUAUAGGACUUAAGACUUUGAAAUGUAAUUUACUUAUAAGGGGAAAUAAUUAUGCUUUAGCACAUCAUUUUAGAAACGUCACAUUUUAGAAACAUUCAGCUUGCUAACCUACAUGUUUGGGAAUUCAUUAAAACCAGUUGUCUAUAUAUUUUGUGCCAUGUAUAUAAGAACAUUACAAUAUAUCUUUUUCUACAUAUGUAGUAUGUGCAACCAGUGGUUCUCAGAGUAUGGUUCUCAGCCCACCAGCUAGUAUCAGUAUCACCUGGGAACUAGUUAGAAAUGUAAAUUCUUUGGCCCCAUCCCAGACAUACUGAGUCAGAAACUCUGGAAUAGGGCCCCCGCAAUCUGUUUUCACAAGCCCUCCAGGUGAUUCUGAUGCACACUUUAAAGUUUAGGAACCACUGGGCUAAGACUCUGUUGAGAUAUAGAGUUUUUCUUCCACUCAGACUGAUAUAGUUAUACAUUGUUCUUCAUGUAAAUUCAGCUUAACCUGGUUAUCUAUAAUCUUUUAUUGGCAAAAGUUAAUUCUCAGUACUGCCUAUAGAGAUACAGUGUAUUUUAUGUACAUACACAAUUAGUCUAAUUCUUGAUAAUUCAGUUAAUUUAGUUUGGCAUUUUCCUACCACUUACUAAAAGGUUUACAUUAAAUGACUGAUUUAAAUAUAUAGGUGCAAUGUUCUAUGUUUAUUUUAAUUGUUAUGACAUUUAAGUAGCUAAUAUAAUUGACCGGUGCUAAAGUCUCCUGUUUAUCCAUAAAAUGGGUACAUUAUGGGCAGUGUAAUACAAGCUUUCUUUUCAUUGCCUAGUACUUUACCAGCAGACCACAGUUUUGCCCUGGCUAGACCAACCCUCAGAACAAAAUCAUCAUUCCUUGUAUUUAUAUUUGUAUCUGAGAUAGUAAACAAGAUGGCUGGCCAGGUCAACAUGGCACCUUAACUUAUUUUUUUAAUAGGUAAAACUUCUUCAAAAGUAGCUUGCUUUGUAUAAGAACUAAGCUAUCAGUAUAGAUAUAGCUAUCCUUGGAGCUUAUGUUUCAGACAAGAAUUAUUUACUAAAAUAAAUAAUAAACAAGAUAAUGCAUUAUACAAUUUGGGCAUUUCUCGUUUCUCAAGUGUAUGCAUCAUGGUAAAUAUAAACUAACCACAAGAUAGGUAGAUUGAUUCAUUUCAUUUUAAUCUCCUUGUGUAAUUCAGUACCUCCAUAAUUGUUCUAAUCUUCUUCCCACUGUUUACAAAUUACCAGUUAAUUAACUCGUGAAAGAAAAAUUCACAUAUCAGAAUAAAAAUAAAUGUAUACUCACUUUAUAAAAAUCACCACUGCUGUCUUUCCUUAAUACUAGCAGUGGAAAUGUAAGUGGCUUACUCUACAAAUUUUGGUGCUGGCAAAUACAUAGGCAAACUGUUGGGAGCUGCUCUAGUUACAUUCCUCCCUUCUUAUUCCCUUUUUCUCUUCCUCACUUUAUUGCAUAACAUAUUCCUGUACCCAAAGCAUUCUACCACAGUUCUAUUUGACUCCCACUUGUAAUAACUCCUUUAAAAAAUUCCAUGUUUAACCAUAUGACCCUGCUUGCUUACUCAUAUUCUCCCUCCCUCUCCCCUUCCUUUCUCUCUCUUCCAGAAGUCAUUUGCCUGGUUUGAAAUAUUUUGUAGGGAUUGCUUAUUAUAUUAUUUUAGCUGAUGAACCUCAGGACAACGUCUACACACACACACAUACAUACACGCACACAAAAUCUCAGCUGUUGAAGAGUGGGCUUGGAAUCAGACUUCUGUGUCCAGUAAAAAACUCCUGCACUGAAGUCAUUGUGACUUGAGUAGUUACAGACUGAUUCCAGUGAACUUGAUCUAAUUUCUUUUGAUCUAAUGAAUGUGUCUGCUUACCUUGUUUCCUUUUAAUUGAUAAGCUCCAAGUAGUUGCUAAUUUUUUGACAACUUUAAAUGAGUUUCAUUCACUUCUUUUACUUAAUGUUUUAAGUAUAGUACCAAUAAUUUCAUUAACCUGUUCUCAAGUGGUUUAGCUACCAUUCUGCCAUUUUUAAUUUUUAUUUAAUUUUAUUUGCUUGAGCACACUGAUCAACCACUGAACUGCCUUCUUCCAUUGUCCUGCAAUGAUAUAAGGGUUACAUUUUUGUGUAUAUGGCUUUCAUAGUUGGGAUUUCAGAGCACUGAUACCAGAUAUUUUCAGUUUGUUCUCUGGGGGAAUUUCAUUUGCAUCUAUGUUUUUAGCUAUCUGUGAUAACUUGUUAAAUAUUAAAAAGAUAUUUUGCUUCUAUUGGAACAUUUGUAUACUCGCAACUAUAUUUCUGUAAACAGCUGCAGUCAAAAAUAAAACACUGAAAGUUUUCA